ACCCAACUCCCCCGCCCGCCCCGUGCAGGCUGUGGAGACUCCCUUCCCGGGGGAGGGGGCCCCCACUGCCGCAGGUGCCCCCUCUGCCUCCACCCCGGUGAGAAGGGGGUGCUGGGGAGGGCAUCUGGAUCCCGAGACCGGCGCAGAUGAUCAGCUUGCAGGAGGGGAUGGGGUCAAAGGUGGAAGGCUUCAAGCUGGCAGGAGAGAAGGGGGCCAGGACCGGGUUUGGGAAGGAGAAGGACAUUGUCUGCCAGGACCGAGAGCAGGAUGGGCAUCCCAGGCCUGGGGCAGGUGGUUGCAGCUGCAGGGGGGCUGCUGAGAGCGGGCAGGUUGAUUUCUGAAUUCCUGGUGGGCAUGGGAGUCAGGCUCCUGGCCAGAAGCUGGAGGGGGCUUGGCCAAAAAGAGGGAGAAACAACUCAGCUGUUCUUUCUAGCUCUGAAAUAGAAAAUGUCUGCAGACGGCGGAGGCAUCCAGGACACCCAGGACAAGGAGACACCCCCGGAGGUUCCAGAUCGUGGACAUCCUCAUCAGGAAAUGCCUUCUAAGCUGGGGGAGGCGGUACCUUCAGGGGACACUCAGGAGUCACUGCACAUUAAGAUGGAGCCCGAAGAGCCACACUCCGAGGGGGCAUCGCAGGAGGAUGGGGCUCAAGGUGCCUGGGGCUGGGCACCCCUAAGUCACGGCUCUAAGGAGAAAGCUCUCUUCCUGCCUGGCGGAGCCCUCCCCUCCCCCCGGAUCCCCGUGCUUUCCCGAGAGGGGAGGACCAGAGACCGGCAGAUGGCUGCAGCGCUCCUCACUGCCUGGUCCCAGAUGCCAGUGACUUUCGAGGAUGUGGCCUUGUACCUCUCCCGGGAGGAGUGGGGACGGCUGGACCACACGCAGCAGAACUUCUACAGGGAUGUCCUGCAGAAGAAAAAUGGGCUGUCACUGGGCUUUCCCUUCAGCAGGCCUUUCUGGGCCCCUCAAGCGCACGGCAAGGGUGAGGCCUCGGGCUCCAGCCGGCAGGCAGGAGAUGAGAAGGAGUGGAGAGGCGCGUGCACAGGAGCCGUCGAGGUGGGGCAGAGGGUGCAGACCUCAUCCGUGGCAGCCCUUGGGAAUGUGAAGCCCUUCAGAACCAGGGCAGGGAGAGUCCAGUGGGGCGUCCCGCAGUGCGCGCAGGAAGCAGCCUGCGGCCGGAGCUCAGGGCCGGCCAAAGACUCCGGGCAGCCGGCUGAGCCAGAUCGCACCCCGGAUGCAGCUCCGCCAGACCCCAGUCCCACGGAGCCCCAGGAGUACCGCGUCCCGGAGAAGCCCAACGAGGAGGAGAAGGGCGCCCCGGAGAGUGGCGAGGAGGGCCUGGCCCCUGACAGUGAGGUGGGCAGGAAGAGCUACCGGUGCGAGCAGUGCGGCAAGGGCUUCAGCUGGCACUCGCACCUGGUGACGCACCGGCGCACGCACACGGGCGAGAAGCCCUACGCCUGCACUGACUGCGGGAAGCGCUUCGGCCGCAGCUCGCACCUCAUCCAGCACCAGAUCAUCCACACGGGCGAGAAGCCCUACACCUGCCCCGCCUGCCGGAAGAGCUUCAGCCACCACUCCACGCUGAUUCAGCACCAGCGCAUCCACACCGGAGAGAAGCCCUACGUGUGCGACCGCUGCGCCAAGCGCUUCACCCGCCGCUCGGACUUGGUCACCCACCAGGGCACCCACACGGGCGCCAAGCCGCACAAGUGCCCCAUCUGCGCCAAGUGCUUCACGCAGAGCUCGGCGCUAGUCACCCACCAGCGCACCCACACUGGGGUCAAGCCCUAUCCGUGCCCCGAGUGCGGCAAGUGCUUCAGCCAGCGUUCCAACCUCAUCGCGCACAACCGCACACACACAGGCGAGAAGCCCUACCACUGCCUCGACUGCGGCAAGAGCUUCAGCCACAGCUCGCACCUCACCGCGCACCAGCGCACCCACCGUGGCGUGCGGCCCUACGCCUGCCCGUUGUGCGGCAAGAGCUUCAGCCGGCGCUCCAACCUGCACCGGCACGAGAAGAUCCACACCACCGGGCCCAAGGCCCUGGCCAUGCUGAUGCUGGGGGCGGCGGCGGCGGGGGCUCUGGCCACACCCCCACCCGCUCCCACCUAGGAGGCCAGGAAAGGGGGAGCGGGGCGCCCAGGGCCACUGGAACAGCCCCACUGGAGUCAAGGCUCCGAGGGAGGAGAGAGGGGCUCGGGAAGGGAGCUGGGGCGGUGAGGGCAUGGGGUGAGGCAUGGCGAUGGGGGAGGGCGAGGGCGAGAAAGGGCAGGCACUCUGCGAAUUAAAGGCCUUGGACUUGAA